AGUGACGAAGUCCAUCCCCGGGUGCGGGAGGCGGGGAGGGGAGGGCAGGCAGAGGAUUUCGCUCGCUCGCCCGCGCGGGAUCCGGGACGCGCCGGUGGCGUCCGCUGGCAGCAGAGACUGUCAAUUUCGGAUCCAAAGACGGCGAUGGCAGAGCUCACCCGGGUUGCCUGUCAAAUCAAGGCUAUCGCAGAAUAAAUCCCGCCGCCUGCCGCGAAGCCCCGGCGCACCGCAAACUUCAGUGAGCGAACUGGGUGAUCGCUGUUGGGAUAUGCAGAUUCCUGAUGUAAAAGGCGGGGUGGCCCCCCCGAGAGCCUCUCCCGGGGGCCGGAGCCCGCAGGUGCAGUGAGGCGCGCGCGCCGGUGCCGGCGCCCCCAGAGCCGCCUUGCCCGGGUAGAGGGAGCCCGGCGCCCGGCGGGGUCUGGCGGCCGCACACCGGCGGCGGCGGCUUGUCUGCGGCGGCUGCAGCGGAUGAUGGUGGCGGCCGGCCCGCUGGGCUGUGCCUGUGUGUCGCCGCGGAAAUCAGCGCCCUGCGCCGCGCGCUGAGCCCCUGCAGGUCCGCCGCAGCCCCAGCCUCGGCGAGGACGGCCCCGGCGCGCGGGGGGGCGGGGGGCGCGCGGGGUCGGCUUAUCAUGGCGGAUCGGACGGCGCCCCGCUGCCAGCUCCGGCUGGAGUGGGUGUACGGGUACCGGGGUCACCAGUGCCGCAACAACCUGUACUACACGGCAGGCAAGGAGGUGGUCUACUUUGUGGCUGGGGUCGGGGUGGUUUACAACACCCGCGAGCACAGCCAAAAAUUCUUCCUGGGACACAACGACGACAUUAUCAGCCUUGCCUUACACCCAGACAAAACUCUCGUUGCAACUGGCCAAGUCGGGAAGGAGCCAUAUAUAUGCAUAUGGGAUUCCUAUAAUGUCCAGACUGUGUCUCUUCUUAAAGAUGUCCAUACACAUGGAGUUGCCUGCCUGGCUUUUGACUCAGAUGGACAGCGUUUAGCCUCUGUGGGGUUGGAUGCCAAAAACACAGUCUGCAUUUGGGACUGGAGGAAGGGAAAACUUCUGGCGUCAGCCACCGGCCAUUCUGACAGGAUUUUUGAUAUUUCCUGGGAUCCAUAUCAGCCAAACAGAGUGGUUAGCUGUGGAGUAAAACACAUAAAGUUUUGGACACUGUGUGGAAAUGCCCUGACUGCAAAAAGAGGGAUAUUUGGCAAAACAGGGGAUCUUCAGACCAUCCUUUGCCUUGCAUGUGCCAAAGAAGACAUCACCUACUCUGGUGCUUUAAAUGGUGACAUCUAUGUCUGGAAAGGGCUCAAUUUAGUCCGCACCAUUCAAGGAGCACAUAGUGCUGGAAUCUUUAGCAUGUAUGCUUGUGAAGAAGGCUUUGCCACUGGUGGGCGAGAUGGGUGUAUACGACUGUGGGACACUGAUUUCAAACCAAUAACCAAAAUUGAUCUCAGGGAGACAGAACAAGGAUACAAAGGCCUCUCUAUCCGGAGCGUGUGCUGGAAAGCAGACCGCCUUCUAGCAGGGACCCAGGACAGUGAGAUAUUUGAAGUGAUUGUGCGAGAGCGAGACAAGCCGAUGUUGAUCCUACAGGGCCACUGCGAGGGUGAGCUCUGGGCUCUGGCCCUGCACCCCAAGAAGCCUCUGGCUGUGACAGGCAGCGAUGACCGCUCUGUCAGGCUGUGGAGCCUGGCUGAUCAUGCCUUGAUCGCCCGCUGUAACAUGGAAGAGGCGGUUCGCAGUGUAGCUUUCAGCCCCGACGGAUCUCAGCUGGCCCUGGGCAUGAAGGACGGCUCUUUCAUUGUUCUCCGAGUCAGAGAUAUGACAGAAGUAGUUCACAUCAAAGAUCGAAAAGAAGUCAUUCAUGAAAUGAAAUUUUCUCCAGAUGGUUCUUACCUUGCAGUGGGAUCCAAUGAUGGCCCAGUAGAUGUCUAUGCUGUUGCCCAGAGGUAUAAGAAAAUUGGAGAAUGCAGCAAGUCCCUUAGUUUCAUCACGCAUAUUGACUGGUCCUUGGAUAGUAAAUACUUACAAACUAAUGACGGUGCAGGAGAACGAUUGUUCUACAGAAUGCCAUCUGGGAAGCCUUUAACAAGUAAAGAAGAAAUUAAAGGGAUUCCUUGGGCCUCCUGGACAUGCGUGAAAGGCCCUGAAGUGAGUGGAAUUUGGCCCAAAUACACUGAGGUUACUGACAUCAACUCAGUGGAUGCGAAUUACAACAGCUCAGUGCUGGUGUCUGGAGAUGAUUUUGGACUGGUUAAAUUGUUUAAAUUUCCUUGUCUCAAGAGAGGAGCCAAAUUUAGAAAGUAUGUGGGCCAUUCUGCACAUGUCACAAAUGUCCGCUGGUCCCAUGACUUUCAGUGGGUGUUGAGCACAGGAGGGGCUGAUCACUCAGUUUUCCAGUGGAGGUUUAUUCCAGAAGGUGUCAGCAACGGCAUGCUGGAAACUGCACCCCAAGAAGGUGGAGCUGAUUCCUACAGUGAAGAAUCUGAUUCAGAUUUAUCUGAUGUGCCCGAACUGGACUCUGAUAUUGAGCAAGAAGCUCAAAUCAAUUAUGAUCGCCAGGUUUACAAAGAAGAUCUACCUCAGCUAAAGCAACAAAGUAAAGAGAAAAACCACGCAGUGCCCUUCCUCAAACGAGAAAAGGCUCCUGAGGACAGCUUGAAACUCCAGUUCAUACACGGUUAUAGAGGCUACGACUGUAGAAACAAUCUGUUCUACACACAAGCUGGAGAAGUAGUCUACCACAUUGCUGCAGUUGCUGUCGUGUAUAAUCGGCAGCAGCACUCCCAGAGGCUGUACCUGGGGCACGAUGACGACAUUCUCAGCCUGACCAUCCAUCCAGUGAAGGACUAUGUGGCUACUGGGCAGGUUGGAAGAGAUGCUGCUAUUCAUGUGUGGGACACACAAACUCUAAAAUGUUUGUCGCUGUUGAAAGGACAACAUCAGAGAGGAGUGUGUGCACUUGAUUUUUCAGCCGAUGGAAAAUGUCUGGUGUCGGUUGGUUUAGACGAUUUUCACAGUAUUGUAUUUUGGGACUGGAAAAAGGGAGAAAAGAUAGCCACAACAAGAGGACAUAAAGAUAAGAUAUUUGUGGUAAAGUGUAACCCACACCAUGUUGACAAACUGGUUACAGUUGGGAUAAAACACAUCAAAUUCUGGCAACAAGCAGGUGGGGGCUUCACUUCUAAAAGAGGAACUUUUGGAAGCGUUGGAAAAUUGGAAACAAUGAUGUGUGUUUCUUACGGACGAAUGGAAGAUCUAGUGUUCUCAGGAGCAGCUACUGGAGAUAUUUUUAUUUGGAAAGACAUUCUACUACUGAAGACAGUGAAAGCUCAUGAUGGGCCUGUGUUUGCUAUGUAUGCACUGGAUAAGGGCUUUGUAACAGGUGGAAAGGACGGCAUCGUGGAGCUCUGGGAUGAUAUGUUUGAAAGAUGUUUGAAGACUUAUGCCAUUAAAAGAUCAGCAUUGUCGACUAGCUCAAAAGGCUUGCUUUUGGAAGAUAACCCUUCAAUUCGUGCCAUCACUUUGGGACAUGGACAUAUCCUGGUGGGAACAAAAAAUGGAGAGAUUCUGGAAAUUGAUAAGAGUGGCCCAAUGACACUGCUUGUUCAGGGGCACAUGGAAGGAGAAGUGUGGGGGUUGGCAGCUCACCCUCUCCUGCCCAUCUGUGCAACAGUGAGCGAUGAUAAAACACUUCGCAUCUGGGAACUAUCUGCCCAGCACCGUAUGCUGGCAGUACGGAAACUCAAAAAAGGUGGAAGAUGCUGUGCCUUUUCCCCUGAUGGGAAAGCCUUAGCGGUUGGCUUGAACGAUGGGAGUUUCCUGGUGGUAAAUGCUGACACUGUUGAAGACAUGGUCUCUUUCCAUCACAGAAAAGAAAUGAUCUCUGAUAUUAAGUUUUCAAAAGAUACGGGAAAAUACCUUGCCGUGGCAUCCCAUGAUAACUUUGUGGAUAUUUACAACGUACUUACAAGCAAAAGGGUUGGCAUCUGUAAAGGUGCUUCUAGUUAUAUUACACACAUUGACUGGGACUCUAGAGGAAAAUUAUUGCAAGUGAAUUCAGGUGCCAGAGAACAACUUUUUUUUGAAGCUCCAAGAGGCAAACGGCAUAUAAUAAGACCUUCAGAGAUCGAGAAGAUAGAGUGGGACACAUGGACCUGUGUCCUGGGGCCCACCUGUGAGGGAAUCUGGCCAGCACAUAGCGAUAUAACUGACGUAAAUGCUGCCAGUCUUACCAAAGACUGUUCCCUUUUAGCCACCGGAGAUGAUUUUGGUUUCGUUAAGCUUUUUUCAUAUCCUGUCAAGGGACAGCACGCAAGAUUCAAGAAGUAUGUGGGGCACAGUGCACAUGUCACUAACGUGAGGUGGCUGCACAAUGACUCUGUGCUGCUCACGGUGGGCGGCGCCGACACAGCCCUGAUGAUCUGGACCAGGGAGUUUGUGGGGACCCAGGAGAGCAAGCUGGUGGACAGCGAGGAGUCAGACACCGACGUGGAAGAGGAUGGAGGCUAUGACAGCGAUGUUGCUAGAGAAAAGGCCAUUGACUACACCACCAAGAUUUAUGCUGUGAGCAUCAGGGAAAUGGAAGGCACCAAGCCACACCAGCAGCUGAAGGAAGUUUCCGUGGAAGAAAGGCAGGGAAUUGUCAAGGGAUCAAGACCACCCGUUAGCCGAGCAGCUCCCCAGCCUGAGAAACUGCAGAAGAACAAUAUCACCAAAAAAAAGAAACUGGUUGAGGAGCUGGCUCUAGACCACGUGUUUGGCUACAGAGGUUUCGACUGUCGAAAUAACCUGCAUUACCUUAAUGAUGGCGCUGACAUCAUCUUCCACACAGCAGCGGCUGGCAUCGUUCAGAACCUCUCCACAGGGAGCCAGAGCUUCUAUCUGGAGCACACAGAUGACAUCCUCUGUCUCACAGUGAACCAGCACCCCAAGUACAGAAACGUGGUGGCCACCAGCCAGAUAGGGACAACACCUUCCAUCCACAUAUGGGACGCCAUGACCAAACACACCCUCUCCAUGCUGCGGUGCUUCCACUCCAAGGGGGUGAAUUACAUCAACUUCAGUGCAACUGGAAAGCUCCUGGUGUCGGUGGGAGUGGACCCUGAGCACACCAUCACUGUCUGGCGAUGGCAGGAAGGUGCCAAGGUUGCCAGCCGAGGGGGUCACCUGGAGCGCAUAUUUGUGGUGGAAUUUCGCCCCGACUCAGACACGCAGUUUGUAUCUGUCGGGGUCAAACAUAUGAAGUUCUGGACCCUGGCAGGCAGCGCCUUGCUUUACAAGAAAGGGGUCAUCGGGUCCCUGGGAGCUGCCAAAAUGCAGACGAUGCUCUCCGUGGCCUUCGGUGCUAACAAUCUCACUUUCACGGGUGCCAUCAAUGGAGAUGUCUACGUCUGGAAGGACCACUUCCUCAUCCGGCUGGUGGCCAAGGCUCACACAGGCCCCGUGUUCACAAUGUACACAACCCUUCGGGAUGGACUCAUAGUGACCGGCGGAAAAGAGAGGCCGACCAAAGAAGGAGGUGCUGUAAAAUUGUGGGACCAGGAGAUGAAGCGCUGCCGGGCCUUUCAGCUGGAGACCGGGCAGCUGGUGGAGUGUGUGCGCUCCGUGUGCCGUGGAAAAGGAAAAAUCUUAGUGGGAACCAAAGACGGAGAAAUAAUUGAAGUUGGUGAAAAAAAUGCUGCUUCUAACAUCCUGAUUGAUGGUCACAUGGAAGGGGAGAUCUGGGGCCUGGCCACUCACCCUUCCAAGGACCUCUUCAUCUCUGCCAGCAACGAUGGCACAGCCCGGAUCUGGGACCUGGCUGACAAGAAGCUGUUAAACAAGGUGAGCUUGGGCCAUGCGGCCAGGUGUGCAGCCUACAGCCCUGAUGGGGAGAUGGUGGCCAUUGGCAUGAAGAAUGGAGAGUUUGUCAUCUUGUUGGUGAACAGCCUGAAAGUUUGGGGGAAAAAACGAGACCGGAAAUCUGCUAUCCAAGAUAUCAGAAUCAGCCCAGACAACCGAUUCUUAGCCGUUGGUUCUUCUGAACACACAGUUGACUUCUAUGACCUCACUCAGGGCACAAAUCUGAACCGCAUUGGCUACUGCAAAGAUAUCCCAAGCUUUGUCAUUCAGAUGGAUUUUUCUGCGGAUGGCAAAUACAUUCAGGUGUCAACAGGUGCCUAUAAGCGCCAGGUGCAUGAGGUCCCCCUGGGGAAGCAGGUAACUGAAGCCGUGGUCAUUGAGAAGAUCACCUGGGCCUCCUGGACAAGCGUCCUGGGAGAUGAAGUCAUUGGAAUCUGGCCACGAAAUGCAGACAAGGCUGAUGUCAACUGCGCAUGUGUGACCCACGCUGGCCUGAACAUUGUCACAGGAGAUGACUUUGGGCUGGUGAAGCUCUUUGAUUUUCCAUGCACAGAAAAAUUUGCCAAACAUAAGCGAUACUUCGGUCACUCGGCUCACGUGACGAACAUCCGUUUCUCUUAUGAUGACAAGUAUGUGGUCAGCACUGGAGGAGACGACUGCAGGUACUAACGUAGCUGACCCAGUUCUUACUCCACAGGCCUGGCCAGCUCUCCCUCCCCAUCUCAGGCAUCCCGUGGGUCAGCCUCUCCCAGGGGCAUGAGGAGGGCUGAUGUGGGGCUAAUAAACAGGAAAUUCCAUGAGUCCUCAUGAAGGCAAGUACUUUCCAAGAUAAGGCAUUUACUCUUUGGUGACUGUCAACCCAAUGGUUGUGACUGGAGCUGUCCUGGGAUGGCAUGGGCAUGUGAUAGCUACUCUGGGCACUGCUGGGGGAAAGGGACAGGUGGAUGACACCCGAGAUGGCUGAUUUGAGUAGAAGCUCUUGGCAGCCCAUGGGCUUUUGUGCAUAAUCAGGAGGUUAGAAUGCAAAUUCAUCUAUAUGUCCUUUUAAGAACUCCCAGUUGAUCACCAGUGUUGGGAAUUUCUUUAUUUACUCUAAAUAGAGUAUAGAGGAACAGGUCUAGGUCAUUCUAACUCACUCAGCUUCCCCAUUUCUGAUGAGCUUCAUUGUAGCAUGAAUACUGGGUUCUAUUCAGCCCAAGCAAAACUCCUGAGGGGAUAAAGAUGAAAUACAGGCCUUCUGAUACUUCCUGGUGGUCUGAGUUAGGUUGUAAGAAAGGCACCUAUAAAGAAUCUCAACCCACUUCCCACUCAAAAGCACUGUGUAUUUCUCAUGGCCUGCCUGGGAGCCCCCAUCUCCAGCCUGCUGUGCUGGCUACUUCUGGCACUUAUAGCCCUUGAGAUAGUACCGCCAGCAGCUCCCUGUGAAGUGCUAACACCCCUUCAAAGCAGCACCAACCCAAUUGUGAACAAGCUAGGAGUAAAAGACGUAAAUGAAUUGGUCACCCCAAUGCAGGGGAUACAGACUUGUUUUAAUAUAAAAAAGAAGUGGCCUUAACCGUGCAGGGCUUGCAGGCCUUUGUAGGCAUGGGAGCAUGCUGUGAUCCCUGGUUCUGUGCUAAACACUCAAAAGGGCUCUCUGACUCAAGUGGAGGUGAUAAACCUUUUCAAUAGUAACAGGAGAGAGUGUGAUAUCAAAGUGCCAGAAGUCCUCACGGACCAACAUUUAGCACAGACAUUCAAACUGCUGAAAGAACCAAACAGAACUCAACUGAAAAAAACAGACCUUUUAAGAAAAGCAAUAGAUCUUAAUUUGGUGGCAAGAUCCCUGGUUUACCUUUUGAAGUCAAAAUGUUCAAUACAUCACCCGAGCUUGACUUUUGAGCACUUGGCAAGAUUGUUUUUUGCCACUUGACACAAGUAUGAUGUCCAGCUAUGCAAAAUGACUGUUUGAUCUGCCUUUUCAGUGUAUUUGUGUGGCGAUGUCUGUAAAAUGCCAGAAGCCUCUUAUGUUAUUGCUGCUGCUGCUACCAGCCAGCAACUGCAGAGGCCAUGCUGAGGUGCCUCCUUGCCACCAGCCGUUGGGAAAUGCCUACCAUGCUGCCCCGGAUGCACAAGCUCAAAACGCUGCAGAAGUUACACAACUGCUCCCAUAAUCUGGACUCUCCAAAACCGUGAUGCCACGAAGGAAGGUCAAGUUUUAAAAUGUUAAAGACUGCUUGCCUCUGUUCCUGAGACUAAACAGUAUACAUACUAACUACAUUGACAAAGAAAUCCUAUCUGAUAAUGUAGCCCGCUGACGAAUUUUGAAGCCUCGGUUACCCUAACCAAUAUGUAGCUUUUAAUUUGCAUCAAAACUUUUACAAAGAUGUUUUGCUAUUGUUUCUAUAUACUUCAAGAAUGUUCAUUUUUACAAAUAAGUUGAACAAGACAGCCUAAGUUAGAUGCACCGAAGUACUAGAAAUAUCGCUAGCCUCUGUUCUCCAGUUUAGCUUUCAAAACCAAAUGAGCCAUGUAUAAAGGAGUUGAGAAACUUAAUUUUUAAAUGUUUCAUUUGCAGAGUUUUAUAUCCAUUAAGUGCCUUUGAAAGUUUCCAGUUGUGUGGGCUGCUGUCUCACCUCCCACCAAUUUCUCCUUUCUCCAUAUGGUGCUAAAACCUCAAAGCUGAGGAGGGCUGCAGGACCCUUAGCAGAUUCAGUGUGUCACCCUUGUCCUGUGUUCACGCCAAGGCUUCCUAAAUGAAAGACAUCGGUUACCUGCUUAUGGGAAGGUGAGCAGCAAAGGAAUUGAAGUUCGGGACAGGGUAGAAUUAUGGGUUUUCAUUGUGUUUCAUGCCAAACCCACAAAAUCCAAAAUAGAAUUCAAGUUAAACAAACUUCUACUACAAAAUGGAAGGGGAAAAAGGCUCAGGAAGGUCUAUGAGAAUGAGCUGACUUAUCUCGUUAAAUCUUAAGAUAAAUGAGGGUAACCCAAGGCUGCACCUUGGUGUACCACCCUGAGUGGAGUUGAGGUGACUUCAUUUGAUUGCUUCAGGCGAACUAUAUAGGUCAAGUCCAGAUUAUAAAAAAAUUAUCUGCAGAACAAAUUGUAAACCCAAGGAAUAGCUGGUAAAUCAAAAUUAUAAAGUGAGUUAGAGUUCCUUGGAGUUGGUUGUAUGACGGAAUAUGACUUGGACAAUCUUUACCAGAAGCCAUCCGUAAGCCCCUCAGUCACACUUUCCAUGUAGCUGACCAGUGACUACAGGAUGUGGCUGACAGUGCUCACUGAAAGGAGAGUUGGUGCGGGACUGGUGGUUCUGAGCACAUAGACGCCUAUUAGUCCUUCUGGUCAGUGAACGAAAAUUCUAGACCUACAGUUACUGGCUACUUGCAUUUGUCAGUUUAGAGAAAAGGUAAAAUGAGGCAUUUUCAAUUGUAGAAUAGACUAACAUUUACCACAGAAGUGCUUCAGCAUUCUAAAUGGAUUAGAUCACUCAUUAAGCUAUUUUUAUAUGCCAAUUUACUAAUGCCUUACAUCAAUCCACUAAUAGGUUGUUGGGCCCGCAGUAGAGUCCCUAUGCAGUCCCAAUUCUGUUUUCUGUAACCAUGUGACUGGUGAUGCAGAGUGAUAACCAUGUCUGCCUAUCUUGUACUAGACUCUUCAUGCUGAUCGGAUCUUGCAUUGAAAUAACCAUGUGGAAGAACAAUGAAUCGAUUAAUGAUGACAUGUACAACCAUAUUUAAAGAGCAAUAGUGUCCGUGUGUCAUGAAAAACUUAUUUGUAAACGUUUAUAUGGUAUGAUUUUGAUUUUAUGUAUGUUCAUAAAUCCUGCACUGUAUGAUAUAUGUGAGUUAAAACAUUGGUGCAUGAAUUUAUUUUCAAAGUAUAAAACACAUCACUUAAACAUUUUAUGUGUCAAAUAAAAUUUGAUUAUGUAAACACA